GAGAUAACUGGGCGAUUCUGACAGGCUUGUCUACACUACCAUUCUUUGACCGGCCGGUGCACACGCACCAACUCCUUCCCCGCAAAUAACGAAGAUGGCCCAGCCCAUCCCAGGGCUUCCCGACCCCCUUCCCUCAGUCCUUGCCCUUGCCCGGAAUUCUUUUACUUAUUUUUGGAAAAUUAGUUAAGACAUCACUACUAGCUAGAUAUAACUUGCUAGCCAUACAAAUUUCGAUGGAAUUUGGACAAAUCAUUUAUAUUCCCGGGCCUUAUUCUCAUCUUAUGAGAUGAUGAAAUUGACUUGAAACUUCCAAAAUGUUGAUAUUGUUCUUUUGACUACUCAAACUACUCUACACUGAGCCCCUGUGGCAUUUAAAGUAACACAUGGUAUAAUGAUCAAUUUAUUGUUUGGCAUAGGUGUCUUGGCUGAAUCUUAUUUUUACCCUAGGAGAACCCCUGGAAGUCGCUUUUUAAAAAUCUGAAAAGGACACCGGAAAUGUCUUUUAAUAUGUUUCAUUUUUCUAAAAACCAAAUACAAUGAUCCCCAAAUCCAACUUAUUUUUUAAUUUUUAUUUUGUUUUUUGUGAAUUGAAAUAGUUUUGGUUUUUGUAAUCUCUGGAGAACAAUAAUAACAAUAACAUUUCUCUUUACGUGUUAAGAGUUUUCCAGAGCUGAAAUUCCAGCAUCUCUAGGUAUUUCAUUGCACCCACUCCAGAAUUCCAGAGCUUUCUACCUACGCUCACCGGUUGAGCCACAUCCUCAGUGUUUUCUCCCUUCUUUGCCCCAUCCAGUUUCGGCGUUUAGAACUGGCUUCAUUUGUGACAGUUCACCUUCAGGACUGGCCUCCCUGAGCUGUAAAUAUUAACAAUAGUAUAGGAGGAGGAGUUAUAGUAACUGCAGUUCUGGCAGGAGAUGAGUGCUACUAUUAUUAUUUAUUGGUAGCUAAUUAUUUUAACCUUUGCAAUUUAACUCUAUAAGGACUUCUGUAGACAAGACAGAUACUGUAAAGACAGCAAAGAACAAACAGAAUGGCAGAUUGCUAAUGUUUGAUCCAAACGAAAAAGUGAUGAUUGAAUCAAACGAAGCAAUGUCAGAUAAAUGCCUCUUUGGACGCAGACCAAGAUUGACAAGCAAACUUAAUACCUCACCAACACAGGUCUCUGUAAAUGUAGCUAAAACAUUCUCAGAAAAGAAGGAAGUCCCUUCUAAGAAUAUUGCAAAUAAAGUCUCUUUACAGACUACUGAAAAUAGAGUAUCUUCAAGGAGUAUCGAAAGUAAAGAUAUCUUAACAAAUCUACAGUCUGACCUAUUGUCAUCUUCCUGCUUAAAAGAAAGCACAGGUGAAGUGAGCAAAGAUGCAGUCAUUGUAAAGCAGGAGAAAAAUAAUGAAUAUUGCCUUCAGGAUAUUGAUGAUAAAUUGUCAGAAUCAGCAGAGGAUGAUGGUGAAGAUGAUACCAAUGAUGAAGAUGAUGAUGAAGAUAGUAACCCUAAAAAGAAUACUCAGGCCCCACUAGAGUUAAUGGCAGAAUUUCUGAGAGCAGAAAUGGCCCGAGAGUACCAGCUGGCAAAAAAAUUAUGUCAGAUGAUCCUAAUCUAUGAACCAGAAAAUCCUGAGGCCAAGGAGUUUUUCACACUUAUUGAAGAAAUGUUGCUGAUGGAGAAAACUCAGAAUCAUGAGCAAGACGGUGAAAACAGUGAUGAAGACAGCAGUGGUGAGAGUAAAGGAGAAAGCGAUGAGGAGCUGAGUGACGAGAGCUCUGACGAAGGUGAAGAUGGAUCAUGAGUGUUGCUGCAAUACUUGAAGCUUCAUGUAUUUUCAUUAAUGUAUACCAUGCAAAUAUAAAGACAAGUGACAUUUUAGUCUAA